AUCCGCUUCCGGUUCCCAGACUGAAUUGUCAGUGAGCGGAGUCUGAGGUCGCUGUGGACUGCCCACUGGAUUGUGAAAAAUGAGGUCCUCUUUCUAGAGUACCUGACAGGUUGCUUGGCAUCCAGAAGAUGUUUAGCUAAGUUAAGAGUUUUCUUCUGUCUUCCUUCUCUCCUCCAACCUUAACACCUAGAUAUGGGCUGGGCCUGUAGACUGACUGCCUUGGAAUGGGUUGGAGCUGCUGUCUGAAACUUGCUGGGCUGCUCUCCCUUUUGAACCACUUUUUGUCUGUUCUGAUUCACUCUUCCAGGGCCUUGCCCGAGAUGGACAGCCGGAUUCCUUAUGAUGACUACCCGGUGGUUUUCUUGCCUGCCUAUGAGAAUCCUCCAGCAUGGAUUCCUCCUCAUGAGAGGGUACACCACCCGGACUACAACAAUGAGUUGACCCAGUUUCUGCCCCGAACCAUCACACUGAAGAAGCCUCCUGGAGCUCAGUUGGGAUUUAACAUCCGAGGAGGAAAGGCCUCCCAGCUAGGCAUCUUCAUCUCCAAGGUGAUUCCUGACUCUGAUGCACAUAGAGCAGGACUGCAGGAAGGGGACCAAGUUCUAGCUGUGAAUGAUGUGGAUUUCCAAGAUAUUGAGCACAGCAAGGCUGUUGAGAUCCUGAAGACAGCUCGUGAAAUCAGCAUGCGUGUGCGCUUCUUUCCCUACAAUUAUCAUCGCCAAAAAGAGAGGACUGUGCACUAGAAAGUUGCAGCCCACAGCCCUUCAUGUGGACUCUGUCAUGACAUGCUAACUAGACUUCAGGGGAGCCACUUCUGUUUUCAGCCCCUCCCUGGAAUAGUGAGUUGGGAGGAUGGGGAGACAGCUAACCAACUGCAUUACCCAAACCAUAUUGCACUUUUAGUUCCCUAGUUUUCUAGGUGAGCUUCAUUCCCUGAAAGGAGGAUGAUGAUAUCUAGGCAUAACCUAGCCUGUGAGGAACCUAGUUAGGAAAGACAACUGACAUUUAUUGAAUAUCAUGCACUAGUCCCUUACAUAUGUCAUAUUUUAAUUAUAGAAAUCAGUAGCAAAAAGAAUCUUGGGGAUUUUCCAUCUGACUUCCCUGGCCAUCUUAUCCCAUCCUUGCACUACCAGAAGAUUCAUACACUUUUGAGACUCCAGUGAGACGCUGUUUUCACCCCUUCCUCCUCCUAGCCUCUCUCCCAAAAAGUAAAACACAAUGCUGAAGAAA